AGUCCCGCCCCUGAGCUCUGUCAUGGCGACGUCCAGUGCUCCAGCCGGUGUGAGGACACGAUAUGCUGGGGUUUUUGUCCGCACGCCAAACGGGUUUGGAGGACCCUCUUCGCCUUCGGAGAGCAGAGUCAACACGGAGAGUUUUGGGACUGGAAUUAAAUAAAGACAGAGAUGUUGAAAGAAUCCACGGCGGUGGAAUUAACACCCUUGACAUUGAACCUGUUGAAGGGAGAUAAAAUGAAGCUUCUUAUCCAAGAUGCUCAAGGAAAUAAAAUGUGAGUCAAGGAUUUUAUAUCCAGCCAAACUGAUUUCAGAUACAAAAAGGACGGAUAAAUUGUCAACAACACAAGAAUUCAGAGACUGUUGUUCUCAUUAGCCAUUCCUUAGGAAUCAACCAGAGAAUGAAAUCAUUCAACCAGAAUGACAAGAGAGACAGCAACUUAAGGAUUGACGCAUGUUAUCAGGUGGUUCAGAUGGUGUGAUUGUACUUUAUGACCUUGAGAACUCCAGCAGACAAUCUUAUUACACAUGUAAAGCAGUGUGUUCCAUUGGCAGAGAUCAUCCUGAUGUUCACAGAUACAGUGUGGAGACUGUACAGUGGUAUCCUCAUGACACUGGCAUGUUCACAUCAAGCUCAUUUGAUAAAACUCUGAAAGUAUGGGAUACAAAUACAUUACAAACUGCAGAUGUAUUUAAUUUUGAGGAAACAGUUUAUAGUCAUCAUAUGUCUCCAGUCUCCACCAAGCACUGUUUGGUAGCAGUUGGUACUAGAGGACCCAAAGUACAACUUUGUGACUUGAAGUCUGGAUCCUGUUCUCACAUUCUACAGGGUCACAGACAAGAAAUAUUAGCAGUUUCCUGGUCUCCACGUUAUGACUAUAUCUUGGCAACAGCAAGUGCUGACAGUAGAGUAAAAUUAUGGGAUGUGAGAAGAGCAUCAGGAUGUUUGAUUACUCUUGAUCAACAUAAUGGGAAAAAGUCACAAGCUGUUGAAUCAGCAAACACUGCUCAUAAUGGGAAAGUUAAUGGCUUAUGUUUUACAAGUGAUGGACUUCACCUCCUCACUGUUGGUACAGAUAAUCGAAUGAGGCUCUGGAAUAGUUCCAAUGGAGAAAACACACUUGUGAACUAUGGAAAAGUUUGUAAUAACAGUAAAAAAGGAUUGAAAUUCACUGUCUCCUGUGGCUGCAGUUCAGAAUUUGUUUUUGUACCAUAUGGUAGCACCAUUGCUGUUUAUACAGUUUACUCAGGAGAACAGAUAACUAUGCUUAAGGGACAUUAUAAAACUGUUGACUGCUGUGUAUUUCAGUCAAAUUUCCAGGAACUUUAUAGUGGUAGCAGAGACUGCAACAUUCUGGCUUGGGUUCCAUCCUUAUAUGAACCAGUUCCUGAUGAUGAUGAGACUACAACAAAAUCACAAUUAAAUCCGGCCUUUGAAGAUGCCUGGAGCAGCAGUGAUGAAGAAGGAUGAAUAUCAUCUUUAGUACCUUUUUGUCUCUGCUGAAACUUUUUAAAUGAGACUGUGUUUUUUUCAACUGUAUGGUCUAUUCCUGACAGCUAAAUUAGCCCUAAAUGUGGGUAAUAUUUUUCCUCAUGUUUUAAAAUGAGGUUAAUAUUUGCAUAAAAUCCUAAAACAGACUUCUGUAUAGUUUAUUUAGUCAAAAUGUGUUCCUUGAUCCCAGAUGUUGUGGCCUGGGAAAGCCCUCAUUGCUACAGUACAAGUAACACAAGUCGUUGUACCUCAGUUGUGACCUUCAGCAGAUUUUAUGAACUAUAAGAUGCAGUCUCAGAGGAUCAGCAAGUGGAGGCCAUCAGUAUUGACUUUCUCUUACUUGCUGUACUAUCAGCCUGCUCGUUUCCACCUUUAAGAAUGAUUUUGCCAAGAAUGAUUAUAUCAAAAAUAGUAGUUGAAAUGGUAACAUCAAAAUUAUUUUAUUCUUUCUUCUUCAUGUAUUCACAUUUUUCAGUGGUUUCAUUUAAUUAACCAUGCUUUAUGUUAAACAUUUUGGGGCUCAAUGUCUCCUACUAUCCAAAAUGUGCAUCACAGGAGGCUUUUAACUUUGUGAAAAUCCCAUGUUUGCUUUAUUUUAUUUUAAUGUCAGAAGGCAGUUUGCGCUAAUGCUUGAACUCUUUUUCUGUGAAACUCAUUAAGGUAUGACCAAAUCCUGCCUCAUUAAUUCAAGCAGAAAAUAUCCUGGCAGGGAAUCUGGCUUAAACAUGAAAUGCUGUAAUAAAAUUUCUAUGUUAUUGUCUCCGUCUGUGUCAACCCACACGUGAUUAUCAUGAAGGUAAUCUUAAUUUUCCCUUCCUGAUCCUUACCAGCAGUAGACUAGUAAAUGAGGCUUUUAUGAGCUUGAAUACCAAAAGUAAACAGUUGUUGAGGGUUUUUUGUUUUUUUGUUUUUUUCCUGAGAUGGAGUUUCACUCUGUCGCUCAGGCCGGAGUGCAGUGUUUUGAUCUCAGCUCACUGCAACCUUCACCUCCCAGGUUCAAGCAAUUCUCCUGCCUAAGCCUCCUGAGUAGCUGGGAUUACAGGCUCCCGCCACUGCGCCCGGUUAAUUUUUUUGUAUUUUCAGUAGAGAUGGGGUUUCACCAUGUUGGCCAGGCUGGUUGCGAACUGCUGACCUCAAAUGAUCCACCCGCCUCGGCCUCUCAAAGUGCUGGAAUUAUAAGCUUGAGCCACUGCACCCAGCCAGUUGUUGAGUUUUUAAGUGUAUAAGGGUUAGACCUCCUAUCAGACCUUUCCAGCUAAAUGUUUUCCAAACACUUGCUUUUACAAUUGAUUUUUUUUUCCAAUUGGCAGAUAAAAUUGUAUGUAUUUACCAUGUACAACAUACUGUUUUGAAGCAUAUAUACAUUAUAGAAUGACUAAAUCUAGCUAACUGACAUAUGCCUCACAUGGUUACCAUUUUGUGGUAAGAACACUUUACAUCCAUUCUCUUAUUUUUCAAAAUUAAUAGUAAUCUUGUAAUUGUAACUAUAGUUACUAUGUUGUGCAAUAGGUCUCUUGCACUAAUUCCCCCUUUUUAACUGAAAUUUUGUAUCCUUUGACCAAUGUUUCUCCAACAACCCUAGCUCCUGGUAACCACCAUUCUACUCUCUACUUCUAUGAGAUCAGCUGUUUGUGUAUAUGUACUACAUUUUCUUUAUCCAUUCAACCAUUGACAGAUGCUUAGGUUGAUACCAUAUCCUGGCUAUUGUGAAUAAUGCUGCAGUGAACCUGGUAGUGCAGAUAUCUCUUUGACAUACUGAUUUCAUAUCCUUUGGAUAUAAGCCCAGUAUUAGGAUUGCUGGAUCAUAUGUAGUUCUAUUUUUAACUUUUUGCAGAAACUCCAUACUGUCUUCCAUAAUGGCUGUACUAAUUUACAUUCCUACCAAGAAUAUGCAAGAAUUCCUUUUUCUUCACAAUAAUGCAAGAAAUCCUUUUUCUUCACAUCCUUGCCAACACUUGUUAUCUUUUGUGUUAUUGAUAGUAGCCAUUCUAACAGGUGUUAGGUGGUAUCUCGUUGUUUUAAUUUGCAUUUCCCUGGUGACUGCUGAUGUUGAUAAUUUUUUCAUAUAUCUGCUGGCCAUUUGCAUGUCUUCUUUUGAGAACUGUCUUUUCAGGUUCUUUGCCCAUUUUUAAAUGGGUUGUUUUCCUGCUAUUGAGUUCCUUAUGUAUUUUGGAUAUUAACCCCCUAUCAGAUCUAUAGUUAAUAUUUUUUCUCCAUUCUGUAGGUUGUCUCUUCACCCUAUUAAUUGUUUCCUUUGCUGUGCAGAAGCUUUUUAGUUUCAUGUAAUUUCAUUUCUGUACUUGUGCUUUUGUUACUGUGCUUUUGAGAUCGUAUCCAAAAAAAUCAUUGCCCAGACCAAUGUCAUGGAGCAUUUUCUCCAUGUUUUCUUCUGAUAGUUUCAAAUCAUUGAUUUAUUAAGCCCAGGCCAUUCUACUUUCAAUCUUGUCCCCUUGGUGAGGAUGCAUUUGACCUUUGAAAAAGCUAGUUUGAAAAAGCUAUUGGCCGGGCACGGUGGUUGUAAUCCUAACACUUUGUGAGCUGAGACAGGCAGAUCACUUGAGCUCAGGAGUUCAAGACCAGCCUGGGCAACAUGGCAAAACCUCGUCUCUAAAUAAAAAAUACAAAAAUUAACCAAGUGUGUUGUGCACACCUGUAGUCCCAGCUACUUGGGAGACUCAGGCUGGGGAAUCACUUGAACCUGUAAAGUCACGGCUGCAUUGAGCCAAGAUCGUGUCACUACACUCCAGCCUGGGUGACAUGGCGAGACCUUGUGUCUCCCAAAAGAAAAAGAAAAGAAAAGCUAUUAAAAUUGGAAAUUUAUUUUUAAGAAAAAGGAAGUCUGCUUCCAAACUGCAAGUAACUGUUUUACUUACUUCUAGUUAUAUAGAUAUAUAGGCUCAUUAUAAAUAAUUCAAACAACAUAAAAAUCUAAAAAGGAAGGUAGUGGUCACCUGGAAUUAUAAUACCAUAAGGUAACCACCACUAACAUUUUCAUGGUCAUUCUUCAUGAAUCUCUUAUGAUACAUAUAAUUUUACAUAAUGGGAUGUUCAACAAGCUGUUGUUAUAAACACCCCUCUCUUUCCACAUUAGUACCACAUUCCCCAGUCCUUACCCCUGCUGCCACAAACCAAGUUAUUAACCUAGACUGUGUUCUUUCAUAUUGCAAUCCUAUAUAUAUCUAUGCAGACAUAUAGGGGAUGUAUUUUUAUUUUGCAGAACUGGGAUAUACAAAGUUUUUAAAUUAUAUUUUGCAGUUACAGCUUAUAUAAAUCCCUCUCUGUCAUUUGUUAUAACAAAGUUAUUCUUUUUGUUAACUGCAUCAUACUGCAUUUUGUGAAUGUCCCCCAGUUGUUUUCAGCUGGUCCCCUGUUCAAGGCUACAUGUUUAUUAGUGAAGACUUGGAACUGUACUAUAUUUUUCUUGGUAUAUUUUGGUGUACAAUUUGUACAAUUUAGUUGUUGAAUAUCAUCUUUUUUUUCCCCUCUGAAAUGAUAGUUUAGCUGGGUAUACGAUUUUUGGGUUGUAGUCCUUUUGUUUUGUUGGUCUAUAGAUAUUGUGCCCACUUUUUUCUAGCUUCUGGUAUUGCAGUUGAGAAUUCCAAAGCCACUUUGGUUUUUUUUCCCUUUGUAGGGAAUUCAUUCGUUACAGCUGGAAGCUUGUAAACUGAGGUUUAAAAGAAAAAAGUAAAAACUUACAGUUUCUUAAUCUCGUCAAGAAAUCUGAUGUCUUUUUUUAUUCUCUUCCGUCACUUCUUAGACUUCUUGGGAGCUCUUUCAAUGAAGGUCCAAACCUUUUCUCAGCUCAGGUAUAUUUUCUUCUAAUAUUUGUCUAAUUGUUGCUUCUCCUUUUUCCUUCUUCUUUUUUGGAUUAUCUAAAAAUUGCAUGUAACUGACCUCUCUAUGUUUCUUCCUUUCUUCCCUUUUUUUUUUUUGAGACAAAAUCUCAUUCUGUCACCCAGACUAGAGGGCAGUGGCGCCAUCUCAGCUCACUGCAACCUCCGCUUCCCAGGUUCAAGCAAUUUUCCUGCCUCAGCCUCCCAAGCAGCUGGGAUUACAGGUGCCCACCACCACGCCUGGCUAAUUUUUUUUUUUUUUUUUUUUUUUUUUUUUUAGCAGAGGUGGGGUUUCACCAUGUUGGCCAGGCUGGUCUUGAACUCCUGGGCUCUAGUGAUCCACCAGCCUCGGCCUCCCAAAGUGCUGGGAUUUACAGGCGUGAGCCACCGUGCCGGGCCUGACUUCGACUUCUCUUUCAUUGUCUUAUCUUUUCGUUUCUCCUUGCCCUUUUUGUUUUGUUUUGUUUCAAUUCUUAGAACUGUAGUUGGCAUGUAGUAGGUGCUUAAUAAUUACUUGUUUUGUUGUUUCUGUCCUAUACUUUGAGAGUUUGUGUUUGAUAUUCAAGGUUACUAAUUCAGGCCUGACUGUGAUAAUUAGGGGAGACUUUUGAUUAUUGUUUUAUUCCCCUCCCCACCCUAAACCCUUGUUUUGUUUUGUUUUGUUUUGUUAAGCACUUGCAAAAAUAUAGUGGAGAAAUAUGGGAGGCUUCCACUUGAAACUUUUUAAUAAUUGUUUAUUCAACUGGUAUUUGUCAACCCUUAUUCACAUUGUAUAUCAAUGAAUCUAUUAUGAAGGCAGCGAUCAUGUAUAACUUCUCUCCAGUGCCUUGUACAUUUUAUAUGUUUUCCUUUCACGCUGUCUUGGCUGUCCUUUCGUCACCUAAGGUACUUAUAUUCUGCCAUAUUUCAAAGAAUACUUAGGCCAUUUGUUCACUUCACUUUGAUUCCAUUUUUAACUAGUCAUUAUGGUACACCUAUGAAAUGCCUAGUUUUAAAAAAAUAUGUAGAAAUAAUAAAUGCACAUUUUAUUAACAUAGCCAUAAAUCUAUUUUUAACCAGAAGCCUAAAAAAUCACAUCGUAGAUCAGCUUGACCUCUCUUUUAAACUUGCUACCAUGCCUUUACUUUAGAAUUAAGGGAACACCUUAAUAGAGAAAAAAAGUUAUCCCAUGAACUGAAGUGUUCCUUGUGUCCAGUUUAUACUAAAAAGCCCCAUUUAAAAUAGAUUUUAAAACCUUUAAAAAAUUCUCUAAAGACAAAACCUUAAACUGUACCAAUUAUAAUAAUAGAUAAAGUAAUUUCAAAACGAAGCUCUUCAGUAAGAGACACAUAGGUUUGUAGAGCUCAGUAUUGGUGAGAGACACACCAUUAGCUUUAUUAUUUAAAAUCGAAAUGAGACAGUGGUAGAAAAAUAUUGCAUCAGCAAACUAAUCUCAAUUAUUUUUCAAAGCAAAAUCACUAUUUCACAAUGGAAAGGAAAACCUCAAAUUAGGUACUUAAAUAAGGGCUACACAGUUUUCAUUCAGAAAUAUUUCAUUACUGUUGAGUAAUAUACUAAUACUUUGUUAUUUCUAUAAAAAUGAUAUAACUACUGAAGACUAGAGAAGCUAAAGACGUUUCUGUGAAUUCUAUAAUUUUUAUAAACAAAUACUUUGGUAAAUUUCCAUUUUUUUAAUUUAAUGUUUUCCAUGUUCAGGUGCUAAUUAUUGAGCCCGAACUAAAAAACUUAUCACUAAAGCAGUAAACUUAAAAUCACUCUAACUAUGCCAGAAAUGGAAUGGCAAGCCUAGCACAAUUAGAAUAUUGCCUGUCGAAAAAUAUAGCAGGGAAAGCUAAUUACAGAAAGGAAAACAAUCACUUUGCUUUCUAUUGUAAUGAAUUUCUGGACAUCGGAAGGUUAAAUCUAGGGCUCAGGAUAGUGCUAGUUCUUCUGUUUUAAUUCUGGAAAAGUAUUAAAUUCAGGGAAGAAAACUAACGAAGUUUAAUCAUAAACAUUUUUUCUUCUUUGCAAAGAAUAUGUGUGUAGUUCUUAAUGUGCUACCUAGAAUCACUGUUGUAAACCUCCUGGGUGCUUAGAAUUAUUACAAAUCAUUUAUUAUAAUACAAAUUUUUCUAUCUUGCUAGCUCUAUCAGCAACAUCCUCAGAUACAGAAGGCAUACUUCUUUUGCUGCCAUGUGGCUUCUUGUUUUUUGUUUUUAUUAAAAGUAAUCACAAAAACUGCAAUUACUUUUGCACCAACCUAAUAAUUAGACAAUUAAAAUUUCAAAGGAAGGGGGUAAAAUUAAAGAACUAUGUUGCGACCUCUCUUAGUUCUCUGUGUGUAGGACUUUUCAGGUGCCCAAUGUCCUCUUGACUGACCACUCCUCAUGAAGAUACUGGUAAACUUUGUGCUAGUGGAUUGAUAACCGCUCUCCGAGUUCAUGCUCUUCUGAGGUCUAGAAAGAAAUGGGUGUCUCUGUCCCAACCUGGUUAGUUAUUCUGUCUCUAAAAACACAAUUAAGUCAAUGUUAAGACUAAGUUCAUUAAGCUGCUCGUGUUUUUAUGCCUUGACAGUUUGUUAAUGGUGGUUGCAUAAGUUUUACAGAACUAGUUUCGUCUUGUUGCCCAGGCUGGAGGGCAAUGGUGUGACCUCAGCUCACCGCAACCUCCGCCUCCUGGGUUCAAGCGAUUCUCCUGCCUCAGCCUCCCAAGUAGCUGGGAUUACAGGCAUGCGCCACCAUGCCUGGCUUAUUUUGUAUUUUUAGUAGAGACAGGGUUUCUCCAUGUUGGUCUGGCUGGUCUCGAACUCCUGACCUCAGGUGAUCUGCCCGCCUUGACCUCCCAAAGUGCAGGGAUUACAGGCAUGAGCCACCGCGGCCAGCCUGUAGUCAGCUCUUUAAGGCAACAAUUUAUUGGCUCAGGUGACUGGCACAAGCCAGUUUUCUUUUGUUCAUUUCAUCCAUUGUGGCAAGGAUUAGCAACAGUACUAAAUGAGAGCUUGUCAACACCUUCUGUAAAAACACCACCAGGAGCAGGAGAGCUGCUUCUCCCAUGUGGCUCAAACACUUAAUUCCAGCUUCUCUACACCCUGCAUGAUGGUAUCAUCCACUAUUGUGUAAAUCUGUAUAUUUUCUAAAUAAAUACACUGUUCAAACUUAUGCUAAAACAAAGAACAUUCCUAAUAAGUCUUUGAGAACUGAGUUAUUAACUUUUAUUGUAAUAUUCUAAUGGUUUCUUACAUAUAUAUGCAAAAUUCAGAGUAUUAUGGAAAAAGUUAUUAGAAUAACUCAGUGAUGAUCACUAUGGACAUUAAAGAAUGGUAAGAUUAUUUUUUUCAUUGUAAUGGCUUUAUAAAGAAAUAAGGCCAGGCGCAGUGGCUCACACCUGUAAACCCAGCACUUUGGGCAUCAGAGGCAGGAGAAUGGCCUGAACCCUGAAGGCGGAGGUUGCAGUGAGCCGAGAUCGCCCCACUGCACUCCACCCUGAGUGACAGAGCAAGACUCUGUCUCAAAAAAAUGAAAAGAAAAAGAAAUAACAGUGGACUGGAAAUCAAAAGUCCUGAGUCUGUCUUAGGUCACUACCAAGGAAACAUAUACAUUUGGAUAUUUUUUUUCCUUCUUUUUUCAUUGGUUAAAAAUGAAGGAAGGGCUGGGCAUGGUGGCUCACGCCUAUAAUCCCAGCACUUUGGGAGGCUGAGGUGGAUGGAUCACGAGGUCAGGAGAUCGAGACCAUCCUGGCUAACAUGGUGAAACCCCGUCUUUACUAAAAAUACAAAAAAAAAAUUAGGCGGGCACUUGUAGUCCCAGCUAUUUGGGAGGCUGAGGCAGGAGAAUGGCGUGAACCCCGGAGGCAGCGCUUGCAGUAAGCCGAGAUUGCGCCACUGCACUCCGGCCUGGACAAGAGAGCGAGACUCCAUCUCAAAAAAAAAAGGAAGGGGACAGAAAACUGGAAUAGAAAAUUAUUAAGGUUCAUUCCUGCUCUAAAAUCACAAAUCAUCAUAUUUUCUAAAGCAUUUAAAAAUGGUAUGCAUAAAUAAUUAGAGGCUUAGGUUCUAAACUAAUUAUAAUUAAAGUUCAUUGAAGGCAGAGGUAGAGUGUCAUUAUAAAAGUUUUAUGAAUUGUCUUAAUACUGAGUGAACACUCAAAUUCUAAUGGAAUGAAUUUUGCCUGAAUUACACUUUUAAAGCAAAGUUUCCAUGUGAAUUAUUAUGGAGCCAUCAUUGAUUACCUAUUUGAUUUUGCAAGUUUAUUCAUUUGUAGAACGGGAAUAAAAUACACCUUACAAAGUUGUAAGAAUAAAUGAAAUAAAGUUCUGAAAUAUAAGAAUCA